AUCGGCGCUUUGCCACUUGUACCCGAGUUUUUGAUUCUCAACAUGUCCGAGACUGCUCCUGCCGCUCCCGCUGCCGCGCCUCCUGCGGAGAAGGCCCCUGUAAAGAAGAAGGCGGCCAAAAAGGCUGGGGGUACGCCUCGUAAGGCGUCUGGUCCCCCGGUGUCAGAGCUCAUCACCAAGGCUGUGGCCGCCUCUAAAGAGCGUAGCGGAGUUUCUCUGGCUGCUCUGAAAAAAGCGUUGGCUGCCGCCGGCUAUGAUGUGGAGAAAAACAACAGCCGUAUCAAACUUGGUCUCAAGAGCCUGGUGAGCAAGGGCACUCUGGUGCAAACGAAAGGCACCGGUGCUUCUGGCUCCUUUAAACUCAACAAGAAGGCAGCCUCCGGGGAAGCCAAGCCCAAGGUUAAAAAGGCGGGCGGAACCAAACCUAAGAAGCCAGUUGGGGCAGCCAAGAAGCCCAAGAAGGCGGCUGGCGGCGCAACUCCGAAGAAGAGCGCUAAGAAAACACCGAAGAAAGCGAAGAAGCCGGCCGCGGCCACUGUAACCAAGAAAGUGGCUAAGAGCCCAAAGAAGGCCAAGGUUGCGAAGCCCAAGAAAGCUGCCAAAAGUGCUGCUAAGGCUGUGAAGCCCAAGGCCGCUAAGCCCAAGGUUGUCAAGCCUAAGAAGGCGGCGCCCAAGAAGAAAUAGGCGAACGCCUACUUCUAAAACCCAAAAGGCUCUUUUCAGAGCCACCA